GAAACUCUGGCAAGUUGCGGGCGCGCGGGGAGCUGUCGCGGGCAGCGCGCCCUCGGGAGGACGUGGCCCCGGCCCCCGCCCGCAGUGGGCCCGACCCUCAUGGCCCUGAGCAAAGGGCUGCGGCUGCUGGGGCGCCUGGGGGCCGAGGGGGACUGUAGCGUGCUGCUGGAGGCGCGCGGCCGCGACGACUGCCUGCUGUUCGAGGCCGGCACGGUGGCCACGCUGGCUCCAGAAGAAAAGGAAGUCAUUAAAGGACAGUAUGGCAAGCUCACGGACGCGUACGGCUGCCUGGGGGAGCUGAGGCUGAAAUCUGGUGGCACGUCUCUGAGCUUCCUGGUGUUGGUGACAGGCUGCACAUCUGUGGGCAGAAUUCCAGAUGCUGAAAUCUACAAAAUCACUGCCACUGACUUUUACCCUCUUCAGGAAGAGGCCAAGGAGGAGGAACGCCUCAUAGCUUUGAAGAAAAUCCUCAGCUCGGGGGUGUUCUAUUUCUCAUGGCCAAACGAUGGGUCUCGCUUUGACCUGACUGUCCGCACGCAGAAGCAGGGGGAUGACAGCUCUGAAUGGGGGAACUCCUUCUUCUGGAACCAGCUGUUGCACGUGCCCUUGAGGCAGCACCAGGUGAGCUGCUGUGACUGGCUGCUGAAGAUCAUCUGCGGGGUGGUCACCAUCCGCACCGUGUAUGCCUCCCACAAGCAGGCCAAGGCCUGCCUCGUCUCUCGCGUUAGCUGUGAGCGCACAGGCACUCGCUUCCACACCCGUGGCGUGAACGACGACGGCCAUGUGUCCAACUUCGUGGAGACAGAGCAGAUGAUUUACAUGGACGAUGGAGUGUCAUCUUUUGUCCAGAUCAGAGGCUCCGUUCCGCUGUUCUGGGAACAGCCAGGGCUUCAGGUUGGCUCCCAUCAUCUGAGACUCCACAGAGGCCUGGAAGCCAAUGCCCCUGCUUUCGACAGGCACAUGGUGCUUCUGAAGGAGCAGUACGGGCAGCAGGUGGUCGUGAACCUUCUGGGAAGCAGAGGCGGAGAGGAGGUGCUCAACAGAGCCUUCAAGAAGCUGCUCUGGGCUUCUUGCCACGCGGGCGACACGCCUAUGAUCAAUUUUGACUUCCAUCAGUUUGCCAAAGGUGGGAAGCUAGAGAAAUUGGAGACCCUCUUGAGGCCACAGUUAAAGCUGCACUGGGAAGACUUCGAUGUGUUCACAAAGGGGGAGAACGUCAGUCCACGUUUUCAGAAAGGCACUUUGCGGAUGAACUGUCUUGACUGCCUGGACCGAACCAACACUGUGCAGAGCUUCAUCGCGCUCGAGGUCCUGCAUCUGCAGCUCAAGACCCUGGGGCUGAGUUCAAAACCCAUCGUUGACCGCUUUGUGGAGUCCUUCAAAGCCAUGUGGUCUCUGAAUGGCCACAGCCUGAGCAAGGUGUUCACAGGCAGCAGAGCCCUGGAAGGGAAGGCCAAGGUGGGGAAGCUGAAGGAUGGAGCCCGGUCCAUGUCUCGAACCAUCCAGUCCAACUUCUUCGACGGGGUGAAGCAGGAGGCCAUCAAGCUGCUGCUGGUUGGGGACGUCUACGGCGAGGAGGUGGCAGACAAAGGGGGCAUGCUGCUGGACAGCACGGCGCUCCUGGUGACUCCCAGGAUCCUGAAAGCUAUGACUGAGCGUCAGUCCGAAUUCACAAAUUUCAAGCGGAUCCGGAUUGCUAUGGGGACCUGGAACGUGAACGGAGGAAAGCAGUUCCGGAGCAACGUGCUCAGGACGGCGGAGCUGACAGACUGGCUGCUCGACUCGCCCCAGCUCUCGGGAGCUACCGACUCCCAGGAUGACAGCAGCCCAGCUGACAUAUUUGCUGUGGGGUUUGAAGAGAUGGUGGAAUUGAGCGCAGGGAAUAUUGUCAAUGCCAGUACUACCAACAAGAAGAUGUGGGGUGAACAGCUUCAGAAAGCCAUCUCACGCUCUCAUAGAUACAUUCUGUUGACUUCGGCACAGCUGGUGGGCGUCUGUCUUUAUAUCUUUGUACGUCCAUACCAUGUCCCGUUCAUCAGGGACGUAGCCAUCGACACAGUGAAGACGGGCAUGGGGGGCAAGGCGGGGAACAAGGGCGCCGUCGGCAUCCGCUUCCAGUUCCACAGCACCAGCUUCUGCUUCAUAUGUAGUCACCUGACGGCCGGGCAGUCCCAGGUGAAGGAGCGGAAUGAAGACUACAAGGAGAUCACCCAGAAACUCUGCUUCCCAAUGGGGAGAAAUGUUUUUUCUCAUGAUUAUGUAUUUUGGUGUGGCGAUUUCAACUACCGCAUUGAUCUUACUUAUGAAGAAGUCUUCUAUUUUGUUAAACGCCAAGACUGGAAGAAACUUCUGGAAUUUGAUCAACUACAGCUACAGAAAUCAAGUGGAAAAAUUUUUAAGGACUUUCACGAAGGAGCCAUUAACUUUGGACCCACCUACAAGUAUGACGUUGGCUCAGCCGCCUACGAUACAAGCGACAAAUGCCGCACCCCCGCCUGGACAGACAGGGUGCUGUGGUGGAGGAAGAAACAUCCCUUUGAUAAAACAGCUGGAGAACUCAACCUUCUAGACAGUGAUCUAGAUGUUGACACCAAAGUCAGACACACCUGGUCUCCUGGUGCCCUGCAGUAUUAUGGUCGUGCGGAGCUACAAGCGUCUGAUCACAGACCUGUGCUGGCGAUCGUGGAGGUGGAAGUUCAGGAAGUCGAUGUGGGUGCUCGGGAGAGGGUUUUCCAGGAAGUGUCCUCCUUCCAGGGCCCCCUGGAUGCCACUGUUGUAGUAAACCUUCAAUCACCGACCUUAGAAGAGAAAAACGAGUUUCCAGAGGACCUGCGUACUGAGCUCAUGCAGACCUUGGGGAGUUAUGGGACAAUUGUUCUUGUCAGGAUCAACCAAGGGCAGAUGCUGGUAACUUUUGCAGACAGUCACUCGGCUCUCAGUGUCCUGGACGUGGACGGUAUGAAGGUGAAAGGCAGAGCAGUGAAGAUUAGACCGAAGACCAAGGACUGGCUGAAAGGUUUGCGAGAGGAGAUCAUUCGGAAACGAGACAGCAUGGCCCCCGUGUCUCCCACUGCCAACUCCUGUUUGCUGGAGGAAAACUUUGACUUCACAAGUUUGGACUAUGAGUCAGAAGGGGAUAUUCUUGAAGACGAUGAAGACUACUUGGUGGAUGAAUUCAAUCAGCCUGGAGUCUCGGACAGUGAACUCGGGGGAGACGACCUCUCUGAUGUCCCCGGCCCCACAGCACUGGCUCCUCCCAGCAAGUCACCUGCUCUCACCAAAAAGAAGCAGCAUCCAACGUACAAAGAUGACGCGGACCUGGUGGAGCUCAAGCGGGAGCUGGAAGCCGUCGGGGAGUUCCGCCACCGUUCUCCGAGCAGGUCUCUGUCGGUCCCCAACCGGCCUCGGCCACCUCAACCCCCGCAGAGACCCCCCCCUCCAACCGGUUUAAUGGUGAAAAAGUCGGCUUCAGAUGCGUCCAUCUCCUCCGGCACCCAUGGACAGUAUUCAAUUUUGCAGACGGCAAGACUUCUACCAGGAGCACCUCAGCAACCUCCCAAGGCUCGGACUGGAAUAAGUAAACCUUAUAAUGUCAAGCAGAUCAAAACCACCAAUGCCCAGGAGGCAGAAGCAGCAAUCCGGUGUCUCCUGGAAGCCAGAGGAGGUGCCUCCGAAGAAGCCCUAAGUGCCGUGGCCCCAAGGGACCUUGAAGCAUCCUCUGAACCAGAGCCCACACCGGGGGCAGCCAAACCAGAGACCCCACAGGCGCCCCCACUCCUUCCCCGUCGGCCCCCACCCAGAGUUCCUGCCAUCAAGAAGCCAACCUUGAGAAGGACAGGAAAGAUUGUUUUUUGCUCUCGCUCUCAAGCUUCUCAGCCUUGCUUACUGCUUCAAAGACAUGAGUUUGUAAGGACAGUAGCAGCCCAAAGACUGGCAUCUGUAGACACAUCUGGAUCUUCCGUUUGAUCUCAGUGUUCUAGUAACGGACCCUCGCCCCUGUCACCGGAAGAACAGUUUGAGCAACAGACUGUCCAUUUUACAAUCGGGCCCCCGGAGACAAGCGUUGAGGCCCCUCCUGUCGUGACAGCCCCUCGAGUCCCUCCUGUUCCCAAACCAAGAACAUUUCAGCCUGGGAAAGCUGCAGAGAGGCCAAGCCACAGGAAGCCAGCAUCAGACGAAGCCCCUCCUGGGGCAGGAGCCUCUGUGCCACCACCUCUGGAGGCGCCGCCUCUUGUGCCCAAGGUACCCCCGAGGAGGAAGAAGUCAGCCCCCGCAGCCUUCCACCUGCAGGUCCUGCAGAGCAACAGCCAGCUUCUCCAGGGCCUCACUUACAAUAGCAGUGACAGCCCCUCUGGGCACCCACCUGCCGCGGGCACCGUCUUCCCACAAGGGGACUUUCUCAGCACUUCAUCUGCUACAAGCCCCGACAGCGAUGGCACCAAAGCGAUGAAGCCAGAGGCAGCCCCACUUCUUGGUGAUUAUCAGGACCCCUUCUGGAACCUUCUUCACCACCCUAAACUGUUGAAUAACACUUGGCUUUCUAAGAGCUCAGACCCUUUGGACUCAGGAACCAGGAGCCCCAAAAGAGAUCCCAUAGACCCAGUGUCAGCUGGCGCUUCAGCUGCCAAGGCAGAGCUGCCACCAGAUCAUGAACACAAAACCUUAGGUCACUGGGUGACAAUCAGUGACCAAGAAAAGAGGACAGCACUGCAGGUGUUUGACCCACUGGCAAAAACAUGACUGAGCAGCUUUGAAGGCUGCAGUCCUAUAGAAUGCAUACCUUCCUCCCUCUAGACAUCCCUCCACCAGAAGAGACAUCUAUUUAAAGGCACACUGGCCAAAACGUUUGUGCAUCUGUCACUCUCGUGUAGUUUACAAAAAUCGUGUCUCUUAUUCAGUAAGAUGGUUACUCAGCCACCAAAAUAUAUUUCACUCAAGGCUUGUACAUCUGAAGUUUGCUCUUCAAGGAAUGGGAACCUUCCUGUUAAAUUCGGUGUAUGGAUUUUAAGAAAGGAAUCUAGCCAAUGAGGUCCAAGAAGUUCUCACCCAUUGAAUUUUUAAAUGGCUGUUCAGUUCAUGUUGUACGUGAUGGAGAUUUGUCUUUUGUUUUAUUUGCAUUUUACAGAUUUGGUAUAACAUUUUGGGGAGCCACCUGAAGGUUGAUGUAUAAAGUAAGGAUUAGAGAAAGAGGUCGUUGUGACCAUUAGUAGCUGUCCUGGCCCACUUAAACAAGGUUACAAAAAAUCAGAGUCGGAAGCAGCCAAAUAGGUCAACCUAAUGACUAGACUGUACAUUCCCAUGAGCCUUCAUGUUUAAGUGUGUACAUGUGCGUUAACCUUGAUGAUGCGUGAAUCCCGAGGGAGCCGGUGGCAUACACCGUUAGCUUAACCUUAGCUUAAACUAGCUGAAGGCUCCUGUGCCAUGUCUUAGACAUUGCAUGCCCUAUCAAUUACUAUAAUCCUGAGCCAUGGUGUGCUACUGAAACCAAUUUUUAUCCACCAUCUAGUCCUUAUUAAAUGAAACCUCACGGAUCCUUUGUUCCGCUUAUAUUCCAUGCAUACCACAUAAAAGCACACAGUGCGAAAACUCUUGCUGAUACGCGAUAUUGAUUCUCAUUGUUAGAAUAUGGAGAGUGUUUCAGCCUCGUCUGUCCGGCUGGAGCUUCGGGAUGGAAAGUGCUAUGUGUCCCUGCAUAUAAGAAUCACCAGGCCAGUGUUUCUGGGUUUGCUUGUCUAUAUGUUUGUCUAUAUUUUUUGCCUAUACAUUUUUCCCACGUUUCCAACAGCACUUCUCACCUAUUCAAUAACUGAAAAAGACAUUACCAUAGUGCUUUACAUUUUUAAAGUAAUGUUACAAGGUCUGGAAUCCAUUUGGAGCAGAUACCGUGUUUUCGCUAUUUAAUAAGAAGUUCAGUAGUGAAAUCUUACUGUACCGCCUGUUGUAUCUGGGAGCCUCGUACAGAGGCUCGCACAGCAGUGAUCAAGUGUCAUCCCUUACGUGACUGGGGGAUGUCUGUCCUAAAAGCUGACUGCUAGGAUAGUAAGGAUCAUCUUGCCUGGGCUAUGCCACUGUCUUGUUACCAAUUAGACAUCUGGAAUUUCAUAAUUAGUUUUCAUUGUCACUGUCAAGAUAUAUUGCAGAUUACUUAAAUAUGGCCAUCAAAACAAAAGUUACAACACGUAUCUCUUUUCAUCUGAAAACUAAUACCUGGAAAAGGAUAAAAAAAAAAAGGAAUCCGUGACCCACAGAGCUAGACAGAUAAGAUGCAUAGUUGACCAGUCAUAAAAGGCGGUGUUUAGGUGAUCAGGAUGCCGUUGGUGGCAUUUACGUGCUUUAUAUGAUUUUUACCUCUGUAACAAACACAAGAAAUAAACAGAAUGGUCCUUAACAGAGUUUGGGGGAGAGAGCAAGAUGGGUUCCUUGGAGAAGCUGAUUUGCCAAGAUGCACAUCGCUAUUAACAGCCAGAGUCAUAAAUGAAAUGAAAUUGAAGAAUUCAUUCAAAUGCUCUUUUCCCUAUAACCUCUUUUCUCACCAAAAAGGAGAUAAAUUUGAAAACAGAUAAAUGUAACAACCAGUCAAAGAAGCAGGGGAAAAGUAAGCUCCUCCAAAGUUGCUUGCAGUGCUGGAAAUAGAUCUCAUUUUUAGGUUUUCUCUUCGUUCCAGAUACCAAAUAAAUGGGACAGAGAAUAAAAUUUUUGUUAAAAUAUGUGCUCAUCUCCUAAGUAGCUCUUCAGAGUCUGACCGUAAGUAAAAACACACAGAAUUGUGUUGACUGGGGGAGGUGAAUCACAAAAAAGUUACGAGGAGUUUAAGAGUUAAAUAUUAUUUGAUCGUGGCUGUCAAAUUUAGUGAACAACAUAGAUUGGAUUUGGAGUUGGUAGUAGGUAUGGUUCUCAUACCAGAAUUCUCUUAAAAAAAAAAAAAAGGACAAUUGGAAUUGCCUUAUUUAUUUUUAAAAUCAAUGCUUACUAGUUGGUAGGAUUCCCAGGUCAGCAGCAGGGUUGAUUAAAUAAUCUUGACAAUGAGCAGCUGCCAUCUUGGGGGAUUUCAUUCUGUGGUUUUUUAAAUGUUUCGUCUUUGAUGCUACCAUCCAGGGCUUCUUAUUGUGACCUUGUAGCCUAUUUUGUUCCUGCUGUUCUCUAACAUGGUGCAGUUCACGCAGACUGGUUUAGGUACUUCACAACUCACCAUUGUCUCUCUGACCCCAAGCCUAGUCCCUUUUACAUCACCAUCUUCUCAGACUUCUUGCCUAUUCUUAAAAUAUGUUUUGGUUAAUGAUUGAAUUAGGACAUCAGCUUAAGCAAUUCCUGUAACGGUUUAACGUUGUUGAAGUUCAAGGCACAUAAUAAAAUUCUCCCUGAUGUGUGUGUAAGUAUAAACAAAGUAAUGUAUCAAAGCGUUCACUUUAUAAUGAAGUCAUUUCAUUGGGAAGGAAAGCUGCAAAGAUUAUUGGGGGACUAGUGAUUAAUAAAAUCCUGUAAUAUUUUUGAAGUGAAAAUUUGUACUGAAAUUGUACAUGAUACCUAUUAAAUGUUUUUGUCUUUUUUUAAA